AGUGCCCCAGGCGGCGAGGAGAGCGGUGCCUUGCAGGGAUGCUGCGGGCGGGAGCACCAACCGGGGACUUACCCCGGGCGGGAGAAGUCCACACCGGGACCACCAUCAUGGCAGUGGAGUUUGACGGGGGCGUUGUGAUGGGUUCUGAUUCCCGAGUGUCUGCAGGCGAGGCGGUGGUGAACCGAGUGUUUGACAAGCUGUCCCCGCUGCACGAGCGCAUCUACUGUGCACUCUCUGGUUCAGCUGCUGAUGCCCAAGCCGUGGCCGACAUGGCCGCCUACCAGCUGGAGCUCCAUGGGAUAGAACUGGAGGAACCUCCACUUGUUUUGGCUGCUGCAAAUGUGGUGAGAAAUAUCAGCUAUAAAUAUCGAGAGGACUUGUCUGCACAUCUCAUGGUAGCUGGCUGGGACCAACGUGAAGGAGGUCAGGUAUAUGGAACCCUGGGAGGAAUGCUGACUCGACAGCCUUUUGCCAUUGGUGGCUCCGGCAGCACCUUUAUCUAUGGUUAUGUGGAUGCAGCAUAUAAGCCAGGCAUGUCUCCCGAGGAGUGCAGGCGCUUCACCACAGACGCUAUUGCUCUGGCCAUGAGCCGGGAUGGCUCAAGCGGGGGUGUCAUCUACCUGGUCACUAUUACAGCUGCCGGUGUGGACCAUCGAGUCAUCUUGGGCAAUGAACUGCCAAAAUUCUAUGAUGAGUGAACCUUCCCCAGACUUCUCUUUCUUAUUUUGUAAUAAACUCUCUAGGGCCAAAACCUAUGGUAUGGUCAUUGGGAAAUGAGUGCUCAGGGAGAUGGAGCUUAGGGGAGGUGGGUGCUUCCCUCCUAGAUGUCAGCAUACACUCUUUCUUCUUUUGUCCCAGGUCUAAAACAUCUUUCCUAGAGAAAACAAAAGGGACUAAACUAGAAAUAUAAAGAGCCCUAUACAUGACAGGUGAUCACGUACUGAAUGAUUUUGAAGUAGUACAAACAAUAAAAAUUCUCAUUCCGCAUCAUCAUGCGGUCCAUGAUGAUGAGGCCGCAA